AGCCUCGCAGCCGGUCCAUUUCCCUCGCGUGCCGCGCUCACCCACCCGGUGAAUGCCCUCUGCUGGGGUGGGGAAGGGAGGGGAGCGCGGGAAGACUGCGAGCCCCUGGCAGCCGGGUCCAGAGCUAGGCCGGGUCCAGCCCCCGGGUUCUUCAUCCGCUACCCAGGUUGGGCAGGCUGUGUGUGGCUCGAAACGGGGCUCUUGAGACGCUGAGCGCGUGGUGCCACCCUUCCUGUCCGCAGCGGCAUGAGCAGCGCCCCCGCGCCGGGCCCGGCGCCCGCCAGCCUCACGCUCUGGGACGAGGAGGACUUCCAGGGCCGUCGCUGUCGGCUGCUAAGCGACUGUGCGAACGUCUGCGAGCGCGGAGGCCUGCCCAGGGUGCGCUCGGUCAAGGUGGAAAACGGCGUUUGGGUGGCCUUUGAGUACCCCGACUUCCAGGGACAGCAGUUCAUUCUGGAGAAGGGAGACUAUCCUCGCUGGAGCGCCUGGAGUGGCAGCAGCAGCCACAACAGCAACCAGCUGCUGUCCUUCCGGCCAGUGCUCUGCGCGAACCACAAUGACAGCCGUGUGACACUGUUUGAGGGGGACAACUUCCAAGGCUGCAAGUUUGACCUCGUUGAUGACUACCCAUCCCUGCCCUCCAUGGGCUGGGCCAGCAAGGAUGUGGGUUCCCUCAAAGUCAGCUCCGGAGCGUGGGUGGCCUACCAGUACCCAGGCUACCGAGGCUACCAGUAUGUGUUGGAGCGGGACCGGCACAGCGGAGAGUUCUGUACUUACGGUGAGCUCGGCACACAGGCCCACACUGGGCAGCUGCAGUCCAUCCGGAGAGUCCAGCACUAGGCUCCACGGCCCCAGACACCUUCCCUGAGGACACUCAAUAAAGGUUCCUGAAUCUUCCUGCC